GGCACAGCGGACACCAGGACUCCAAAAUGGCGUCAGUUGUACCAGUGAAGGACAAGAAACUUCUGGAGGUCAAACUGGGGGAGCUGCCAAGCUGGAUCUUGAUGCGGGACUUCAGUCCUAGUGGCAUUUUCGGAGCGUUUCAAAGAGGCCCUGGAGGGACAGGAAAGCCAGAAAUGGACUUCGUGAGACUCGCUCGACUGUUCGCCAGGGCCCGCCCCAUGGGACUGUUCAUCCUGCAACACCUGGACCCCUGUAGAGCCAGGUGGGCAGGAGGCAGGGAGGGGCUGAUGCGGCCAAUGUGGGCGCCCUUCAGCAGCUCCUCCUCUCAGCUGCCCCUCGGCCAGGAGCGUCAGGAAAACACGGGCAGCCUGGGCUCUGACCCGAGCCACUCCAACUCCACGGCCACGCAGGAAGAAGACGAGGAGGAGGAGGAGAGUUUUGGGACCCUCUCUGACAAAUACUCCUCCCGGAGACUAUUCCGCAAAUCCGCAGCCCAGUUCCAUAACCUGCGGUUUGGGGAACGGAGAGAUGAGCAAAUGGAACCGGAGCCCAAAUUAUGGCGAGGCCGGAGAAACACCCCGUACUGGUACUUCUUGCAGUGCAAACACCUGAUCAAGGAAGGGAAGCUGGUUGAAGCCCUGGACCUGUUUGAGAGGCAGAUGCUGAAGGAGGAGCGAUUGCAGCCCAUGGAGAGCAACUACACGGUGCUGAUUGGGGGCUGCGGGCGGGUUGGCUACCUGAAGAAGGCCUUCAACCUCUACAACCAGAUGAAAAAGCGGGACCUGGAGCCCUCGGACGCCACCUACACGGCCCUGUUCAACGUCUGUGCCGAGUCCCCCUGGAAGGACUCAGCUCUACAGAGCGCCCUGAAGCUCCGGCAGCAGCUGCAGGCCAAAAACUUCGAGCUCAACUUGAAAACAUACCACGCGCUGCUGAAGAUGGCUGCCAAGUGCGCAGACCUUAGGAUGUGCCUCGAUGUGUUCAAGGAAAUCAUCCACAAAGGGCACGUGGUCACAGAGGAGACCUUCAGUUUCCUGCUCAUGGGCUGCAUCCAAGACAAGAAGACAGGCUUCCGGUACGCCCUCCAGGUGUGGCGGCUGAUGCUGAGUCUAGGGCUACAGCCGAGCCGGGACAGCUACAACCUGCUGUUGGUGGCAGCUCGGGACUGUGGCCUAGGGGACCCCCAGGUGGCCUCAGAGCUGCUUCUGAAGCCCAGGGAGGAGGCGACUGUGCUUCAGCCCCCAGUGAGCAGGCAGCGGCCAAGGAGGACAGCCCAGGCCAAGGCAGGCAACCUCAUGUCAGCCAUGCUGCAUGUGGAGGCCCUGGAGAGGCAGCUGUUUCUGGAACCUUCUCAGGCACUUGGGCCUCCAGAGCCUCCGGAAGCCAGAGUGCCCGGCAAGGCCCAACCAGAGGUGGAUACUAAGGCAGAGCCCAGCCACACAGCAGCCCUCACCGCAGUGGCCCUGAAGCCACCUCCCGUGGAGCUGGAAGUCAACCUCCUGACCCCCGGGGCCGUUCCCCCUACAGUGGUCUCCUUUGGAACGGUGACCACCCCAGCUGACCGGCUGGCCUUGAUAGGGGGCCUGGAGGGCUUCCUGAGCAAGAUGGCAGAGCACAGGCAGCAGCCCGACAUCAGGACCCUCACGCUACUGGCCGAGGUGGUGGAGUCCGGGAGUCCUGCAGAGUCCUUGCUGCUGGCCCUCCUGGAUGAGCACCAGGUAGAGGCCGACCUGACAUUCUUUAACACGCUGGUGAGAAAGAAGAGCAAGCUGGGAGACCUGGAGGGGGCCAAGGCGCUGUUGCCGGUCCUGGCAAAGAGGGGCCUCGUCCCCAACCUGCAGACAUUCUGCAACCUGGCCAUCGGGUGCCACAGGCCGAAGGACGGUCUACAGCUUCUCACAGACAUGAAGAAGUCCCAGGUGACCCCCAACACUCACAUCUACAGUGCCCUCAUCAACGCGGCCAUCAGGAAGCUGAACUACACCUAUCUCAUCAGCAUCUUGAAGGACAUGAAGCAGAACAGGGUCCCGGUGAACGAAGUGGUCAUCCGCCAGCUGGAGUUUGCAGCCCAGUACCCUCCCACCUUUGACCGGUACCAAGGGAAGAACACCUACCUGGAGAAGAUUGACGGCUUCCGAGCCUAUUACAAGCAGUGGCUGACAGUGAUGCCCGCAGAGGAAACCCCGCACCCCUGGCAGAAGUUCCGGACCAAGCCCCAGGGGGACCAGGACACCGGCAAGGAGGCUGAUGACGGAUGUGCCCUUGGGGGCAGGUGAUGGGAGCACAGCUGGAACAAUGUGCUCGGCCCCCAGUGCUCUGUGGGAGCCCCAGGACAAGUGAGCUGGUGUCACCUCCUGCCUGGGGGAAGAGCCAGGCCCUGAGGAACAGCCGCAGCGUGUCACAGGUGUUGGUGAGGACACACACUAGGCCCAAGGUGCCUGUGCUCCCAGCAGGUCCAAGUGCAGCUCCAGCCACCUUUGCGUGUCACCUUCACGGGACUUCCAGCUCCAGCUACCUUUGUGUGUCACCUCACACACCACAAGGGGGCUGGGGCAUCUGGUCCCUGGGGCCUGGGCCGCCCCGCCGGGUUCCAUAGGCCGAUGCUCUGAAAGAAGAGACGUGGGGCUCGAGAGAUUUAAAGAUUUUAUUUUUACAAAUCACAGCUGAUAGACAGCGAAGCCUUCCCCAUAGAGACCGUGCUCCAACUCGGGCCUGGGGCACUGCUCGCUGCUCCCAGGAAGGGGGUGGCGUGACAGGCAGGAACCUGCGAAGUCCAGAGUCCAGGGUGGAGCGCGCCAGCCUCAGCCAGAGCAGCCACGACAGCCACAGUGUGUGCACUCGAUGAUGCGGCCCUGCAACGGAGGAGGACAGUGAGACGAUGCCACUGCGCCACGCUCGCCCCUGCACACUCACAUAUGUGGCAACCCUCCCACGAAGGACCUGCCACCAUGCCAUAUAGGGACACACCUCAGAAACCCUUCCUUGACAGCUCUGGACAGGGAAAAUUUGGCUCCCUCAUGAAGGUAGAACCAGCUGCUGUUGACACCGAGGUUACAUCUGUAUGUCUAUUUAUAAUAUGUUCUGCAAAUCCAACACACGUUUGCCAAUCAAGAAAAAGAAAUCGGUGUGAAUGAGUCUCGUUAUUCUGCUAAGUGAGCAUGACAGACCCUGCGAUGAGCAGACGUGGCUCUGCUACUGUUUGGGGACUUCAGGGGGGCCUCUGGGCUGGUACACUCUGGUGGGGGAAGAGGGCAGGAGACUAUGCACUUGAGUCACACCCUUCUGGCCCAGAGCCCCCCAGAAAGAAGGGUCUUGUCCCCCAGGCCUGGUGCGGCCCAACACUUGGCCAGCCAGAAAGCCCUAGAACAGUGGCUUGUGUUUAUUUUACUUUUUCAAGUUCUUUUUUUGGAAGAACAAGACCAUAGUUUAAGUAAACAGGAUCCUCUGGUGAAACCCAGGUAAGUCUACAGCGGGCUGUUUUGGCCACAGGGCUGAAGCAGCACCCCAGCCCACCAGCCCCUGACCUGGACUCCUUGUGGAAUCUGGGCACUCAGAGGAAGGGGGCUUCUGCCACUCUGCCACCUGUCCCUGCCUCCAUCAGAAAACCAACACCCCAGUCUUCCGUCGGGGAGGCGGCCCUUGCUCGCCCCCACUGCUCAGUACCCAAGUCCUCAGCAUCCAGCCACAGCUCUCCAUUGUCAGUCUCACUGCAGCAUAAAGGGGACUCAUGUGAAGAGGCCCCUGUGUGGAGCUGGGGAAAAGAAGGCCAGGCUGGCAGAUGGGCGGUGGGGCCAACAACUGUGCUGAGGGGCUGCACUGAGCGGCCACUGCUGUGACUCUGCCUCGGGCCACAGCUGCCUUUCAGAGGGGCUUGGAACCGGAUGGAGCUCAGCUCCUGUCCCUCAGCACCACUCCUGAGGCGCCUGGCCUAGGAGUGGUACUUGGAACAGAAAGUUCUGAAAGAAGAAACACAGUGGGCUGGGCGCAGUAGCUCAUGCCUGUAAUCCCGGCACUUUGGGAGGCUGAGGCGGGUGGAUCACCUGAGGUCGGGAGUUCGAGACCAGCCUGAGCAACAUUGAGAAACCCCGUCUCUACUAAAAAUACAAAAUUAGCCAGGCGUGGUGGUGCAUGCCUGUAGUCCCAGCUACUCAGGAGGAUGAGGCAGGAGAACCGCUUGAACCCGGGAGGUGGAGGUUGCAGUGAGCCAAGAUGGCAUCACUGCACUCCAGCCUGGGCGACAAAGCAAGACUCCGUCUUGGGGGGGCGGGAAAGAUAGUGAUGGUAAUGUUAAAGUAUCACUGUGAGGACUGAAAGGGACAGGAACUCACUGGUUGUCCUUCCCUGAUGUCACCCUGCCACCACCUUGGGAUUAGGGCUCCCCACCACCAUUUCCUAAGUGAGGAAAGGGGUUCAGUAAUUUGCCCAAAAGUGGAGUUGAGAUUGACCCCAGACCUAACAAACACACAGCCACACGCUGCCUCACAUGGAUUCCUGAAUACAGGGACCCACUCCCACGAGGGAGAGCCAGCAGGACAUCCAGGGACAAAACGACAUUCCAGCCCAACCAAAUAACAUAAGAUCCCUUGCAGUCGACUAAGGCAGAAUUUUGAGCUGAAAACAACACCAAGCUUGAGUGUCAGACAUUACCACUUCCAGCUUGCUUUUGGGCACGCGGCAGAUGCAGUUCGUCCCGAAGUUGGUGUCCCGUGUCUGAAUGCACCGCAGGCAGCACAAGUUCUCAUAUCCUUGCUUUUUCCAUUUUGCAAUCAGGUUUUUGUCUGCAUAGCCUUCUUUAAUACAAUAUUCAUAGAGUUCUGUCAAAAAGAUGGGGAAAGAGCAUCAGGCCAUGGUCUAAAAACCUUCCCCACCCUUGAUCAAAAAAAGCAUUCAGGCCGGGUGCAGUGGCUCACACCUGUAAUCCCAGCACUUUGGGAGGCCGAGGCAGGCGGAUCACCUGAGGUCAGGAGUUCAGGACCAGCCCGGCCAACAUGGUAAAACCCCGUCUCUACUAAAAAUACAAAAAUUACUCGGGCGUGGUAGCAGCUGUAAUCCCAGCUACUUAGGAGGCUGAGGCAGGAGAAUCACUUGAACCCAGGAGGCGGAGGUUGUAGUGACCUGAGGUCGUGCCACUGGACUCCAGCCUGGGUGACAGCGAAACUCCAUCUCAAAAAAAAAAAGGCAUUCAGUAUUGCAACGGGACAGUCCUUGGAGGAGGAACAAAAAAAAAAAGUACUUAGGCCAGGCAAGGUGCCUCACACCUGUAAUCCCAGCACUUUUGGAAGCCAACGCCAGAGGAUCAUUUGAGUUAAGAAACCAGCCUGGGCCAAGGGCCCAUCUCCACAAAAAAUUUAAAAAUUAGCUGGGUGUGGUGGUGCACACCUGUAGUCACAGCUACUCAGGAGGUUGAGGUGAGAGGAUCCCUUGAGCCCAGAAGGUUGAGGCUGCAGUGAGCCAUCAUUGCACCACUGCACUCCAGCCUGUGGAACAGAGCAAGACCCUGUUUC